GCCUUUUUGUUUUGGAGCUGCCUUCUCGCUGGCGGAGCGGAGGGUCUGCGAGCGCCGGGGAAGGCAGGCUGGGGGCGCAGCCCGCCCCCCACUGGCCGGGCCCCGCAGGGCGGAGAGGAGGACGGACGGACAGACGGCUGGCCGCGCCAUCUGCUCGCCGGAGCUCACUCUCCAAACUCCAAACUGUUGAGUGUGUGCGUGCACGCGAGGGUGGUGAUCGGGGGUCGUAAGUCCCGGGUGAGGAACCGGUUUCUGCUGGGGUUACCUUUGGACGGGGUUCCUGGGAUUCAGAGCAGGGUCAGCGUCAGGCUCAGAAACUGCUGAGGAAUUAGGCAAACAAAAGAGACCACUCAGCGAGUGGCUAGAAGUCGCCCGACAGCCUCGUCGCGCCCCCUCCUUCCUCCGGGGUUGGGGCUGGCCACUUCUGGGGCGGGGAGAGGGCGCCCGAGCCGGCGGGGGCUCCGGCUGCGCAGCCGGGGUCGAAGAGUUGGCGGCCUGUUGUGUAAGCCUCAGUCCUUGUUUUCCCGGCCUGGCUCGUUGUGAAGCCGGACACAUCCACCCUUGGACUCGAUUCAGGCGGCUGCUGCUUUUCUCCUUGCCCCUCUUGGAUUUUCCGGAUUUUUGAAAACCCAGUGGCCCAGGAGCAAGAGGAGGAAGGAGGAAGGGGCAGAUCUGCAGAGGAAUGUGAGAGCCUCCCAAAGCGAGAGCCGCCAAAAGAAUCUGGGAGCCAGAGGGACAGCCGAGCCCUGCCCGGGUUUCUGGAAUGGUGGUUUCAGAGUGAGUCUCUUCUAUUUUAGAACGUUGUUCCAGUGGAAAGUGUCGAAUUUUUCCCCUCGCAGGGCAGAUUUCUCCAGGUCACUUGACUUUUCUUCUGGGAGUAGGAGUUAGGAGAGAUUCCCCUCUAACCCCCCAGAGGCUGCUAAGGGAGGAGGAGACUGUGGACAUGAGCCCUCCCUGCUCACAAGCAUAUGCCCGGAGACCUGAUAGGGCAGUUUCUGGGCCAUGGACAUUGCUUUGAAGAGGGGGAGACUGGACAGCAUCUGUGGGUGCUGAGACCCCACCUUAGGACCUGAGAGAUUGAACUGUGUAAGCGCCAUUCAGCUGCGAGUGCAUUCUUGGACUGCCUUGUGAGCAUCCCCGGUCUGGGCAGGACCCUCUCCUUCCCAUCUUUCUAUACCACCCAGCCCAGCCAUGGCACUGAAAGGCCGAGCCCUCUAUGACUUUCACAGUGAGAACAAGGAGGAAAUCAGCAUCCAGCAGGAUGAGGACCUGGUCAUCUUUAGCGAGACCUCACUGGAUGGCUGGCUGCAGGGCCAGAACAGCCGUGGGGAGACAGGGCUCUUUCCUGCCUCUUAUGUGGAGAUCGUCCGUUCUGGCAUCAGCACCAACCAUGCUGACUACUCCAGCAGCCCUGCAGGCUCUCCCGGAGCCCAGGUGAGCUUGUACAACAGCCCCAGUGUGGCCAGCCCAGCUAGGAGUGGUGGGGGCAGUGGCUUCCUCUCAAACCAGGGUAGCUUUGAGGAGGAUGAUGAUGAUGACUGGGAUGACUGGGACGACGGAUGCACAGUGGUGGAGGAGCCACGGGCUGGUGGGCUGGGCACCAACGGGCACCCUCCCCUCAACCUCUCCUACCCUGGUGCCUACCCCAGCCAGCACAUGGCCUUCCGGCCCAAGCCACCACUGGAGCGGCAGGACAGCCUGGCAUCUGCCAAGCGAGGCAGUGUGGUGGGCCGUAACCUCAACCGUUUCUCAUGCUUUGUGCGUUCUGGAGUGGAGGCCUUCAUCCUGGGUGAUGUGCCCAUGAUGGCCAAGAUCGCUGAGACAUACUCCAUUGAAAUGGGCCCUCGUGGCCCCCAGUGGAAGGCCAAUCCCCACCCAUUUGCCUGCUCUGUGGAGGACCCCACAAAACAGACCAAAUUCAAGGGCAUCAAAAGCUACAUCUCCUACAAGCUCACACCCACCCAUGCUGCCUCACCCGUCUACCGGCGCUACAAACACUUUGACUGGCUCUAUAACCGCCUGCUACACAAGUUCACUGUCAUCUCGGUGCCCCACCUGCCUGAGAAGCAGGCCACUGGCCGCUUCGAGGAGGACUUCAUCGAAAAGCGGAAGCGGAGACUCAUCCUCUGGAUGGACCACAUGACCAGCCACCCUGUGCUCUCCCAGUACGAAGGCUUCCAGCAUUUCCUCAGCUGCCUGGAUGACAAGCAGUGGAAGAUGGGCAAACGCCGGGCGGAGAAGGAUGAGAUGGUGGGUGCCAGCUUCCUGCUCACCUUCCAGAUCCCCACCGAGCACCAGGACUUGCAGGACGUGGAAGAUCGCGUGGACACUUUCAAGGCCUUCAGUAAGAAGAUGGACGACAGCGUCCUGCAGCUCAGCACUGUGGCAUCAGAGCUGGUGCGUAAACAUGUGGGGGGCUUCCGCAAGGAAUUCCAGAAGCUGGGCAGUGCCUUCCAGGCCAUCAGUCAUUCCUUCCAGAUGGACCCCCCCUUUUGCUCUGAGGCCCUCAACAGUGCCAUUUCUCACACGGGCCGUACCUAUGAAGCCAUCGGGGAGAUGUUUGCUGAGCAGCCCAAGAAUGACCUCUUCCAGAUGCUGGACACACUGUCUCUCUACCAGGGCCUGCUCUCCAACUUCCCUGACAUCAUCCAUCUACAAAAAGGCGCCUUCGCCAAGGUGAAGGAGAGCCAACGCAUGAGUGACGAGGGCCGCAUGGUGCAGGACGAGGCAGACGGCAUUCGCAGGCGCUGCCGCGUGGUGGGUUUCGCCCUGCAGGCCGAGAUGAACCACUUCCACCAGCGCCGUGAGCUCGACUUCAAGCACAUGAUGCAGAACUACUUGCGCCAGCAGAUCCUCUUCUACCAGCGGGUGGGCCAGCAGCUGGAGAAGACCCUGCGCAUGUAUGACAACCUCUGACCGCGUGUGCCUGGGCCCCCUCCUUCCCCUGGGCCUGGUCACUGCAGUGUACCCCACUUUCCCGACCUCCCUAUACCAGCAGUGACUGGGGGAGGGGUCAGCGGUGGGGGAGAUAAGCGGCCUGUCCUGCCUCCUGGGAGAAGGAGCUUUCAAGGAGUCAUGGGUGCCCCUGGGAAAUUCCCCACUCCUUAGAAGUGGGGCACAGCAGGGGUGAGAAUAGAGUCAGGAGCCCUCGAGGCCAAGGCCUGGGCUGCCGGUCAGUCAGUGAAGGUCAGGCCAGGGUCUCAGCCUCCCCUAGAGCCUAUUUUGCUUGCUCACCUGGCCACUGCUGCCUUAUCCAUUCAGCAGACACCGAGGCCUGCUGCACCCUUGGGUCGGAUGCUGGGCACCCAGGGCUGUGACAUGCCUGCUCUUCAGGAGUCCUCAGUGAAGGUCGGGGUCAGACACAGACAGAGUCAAUGCAGUAUGACUGAUGUUUAAGUGAGGGAUUUCUGGAAGCUCAUAGAAGGGACCACAGCAUUCCACUGGUCAGGGAAGACUCCAUAGAGUAGGCAACAUUUGGGCAGUGUUUUGAAGAAUGACAAGGGCCUGCCAGACAGUACAUGGGGGAGAAGGACUUUCAGGGGAGAGGAACAGCAUGGGCAAAGUUAUGGAGGCAUGCAAACAUCUCCCUCUUCUCUCCCUUACUUUCCAAGCAAGUUAGGUACGCUUUCCAUGGGGAUUCUGGCCUGUGUGGUAGGAAGGGAUCUCCCUUGCUCCCAUGUUGCUGGCUGUCCGUACAUCACCCUGUCCCCUGCAGGAGGGGGCUACAGGCCAUCUCCCUCCUGUAGGCCUCUGACUCCCCUCCACUUUUGGGCCCUCAGCUUAUCUCGGGCAGGGGACCAUUGCAGCAUCCUCCCCUCCUCGGACUCAAGGUGCUGAGGUAUAAGCCCUGGGCCCCAGAUCCCUGGUGACACCUUCCUGGAGAAGACUCUCAAAAGUGACUGUAUAUUUGAGUUCACCAGCAAUAACUCCCCACACUCGAAGCAGGUCCAAACCCAGGAUCUCAGGGUCCUUGGGCUCUGUGGCACUGUCUUCCCAAGAUCCUUCCUGUUGCACAAUGGGAAACCUAAGAGGAAAAAGACAGGGGCCUGCUUGCCCAGCCAUGCGAGGGAUUCCAUGCCCACCUGCCCUCUGUCUGCCUCGCUGGAAUGUGGGCCCCUGCUCCCCGUCAGGUUGUGCUGUCUCUGACCUAUGUUUACAUCCCCGAGGGGUUUCUGCCUCCUCCCCACCCAGGUCAGGGUGUGGUCCAGCAGCUUGCUGUGGGGUGCUGACAUGUGUCACCACUGCCCCCCUUGCCCCCGGGGGGGUCAUGGUCUCCUCCUGGAUGCUGCUCCUUGAAUCUUUUUUCUUGAUAAACCUUUUACAAUUAAGAUAACACAAGCAUGACUUUUUCUGUUUGGAUCCCAGAAAGGCGGAGGGCAGGAGAAGGAUAGAGCCCUAAUUGCUCCUGAGAGCCAUUGGAUGAGAUUCUGAGGUCGUGGUGGGCACAAAUUUUCCACAGAACCUCAAAAGUUCAGGGGAGGGCUAUGCUGGUGGAAGGUGCCAGCAGGCAGGAGGAGCUAGAGGCGGCUGUGGACCCCUGGGUGGAUCCAUCCCUCCCUAGAACGCACUCUUGUCUCUAAAACAGGUGGAGUGCUGCCCAGGGGACUGGCUGUACUGCCUUGUGAUCUGGGGCUGAGGGUUGUAUGAGGAAGGGACAGGACGCUGUGCCCUAGGACAAUUAAUAGAUGGUGGCUCCUCUCCCCAAGGAGCCAUGCCCUGGCCUUGCCCUUGAAAAGCCCUAGUCCAGGGGAGGGAAGUGGGGGACUCAGAAGCUGUGUCUCUUCCCCAAACCGUCCUGGGUACCCAGCCCUGCGGAGGCUCCCACAUUGGAAACUGAAGAGGACGCUGGCUGUUGGGGGUGCCCUGAUCAGGAUGAGCGGACCUUGCUCUUGGAUCUGUUCAUCCACAGAUGAGAGGAGGGUACUGGUUGAGACUUGGCUCUCCUUUGGAGGCAAUGGGGACUUGGUGGAGGGAGGGCUUCCAGGGUCAAGGCCGUCAGGGAAGGUUGGCUAGACCAGGGACCAGGGAGCUUGUGCAGGAAGAUGGAGAAGGGCCAGCAGGUGCGGUGGGGGAAGGGGCGGGCAGGACUCCCUGUUCAGGGCAUAGCGUCCUCAGAGGAACUUCUGGAAUGGGUCCCCCUGGCCCUUGGUCAACAUUAGGUCAGAUUUGGGACUUUCUGAGGAAUUUUCCCCUCUCUCCACCCUGCCCCAUUUUCUAACCCAUCCGAGGAACUUCCCGCCCUUAACCUCUUCUCAGCUCUGCCAUCCAUGUAGCCAUCUGCAGAAGGGGCUCUGAGCAGUGGGGGCUGGGCCAGGCCGAGGCAGGGCUGGUGGGAAUGCUCCUCCUAACCCAUGGUGCCUGGAAAGUCCCCUGCUCAUGCUUCCUGCUCUGGGAACAGUGUUGUCCUCUGUGUGCCUUCCUUGAGAGGGGACCACCUCCCAGGCCUUCCAUCCUCAGGGUGAGGCCAUCAGUCUGAUACUUUUCUCAGGAGGGACUUGGAUCCAGGAGAAGCAUCAGGAAGUGGAGUCUUGGGAUAAUGCCAGGCCUGCUCCUGGUAUCCUGAGGUCUCUGGGCUGGGGCAGGUGUGUGUGUGGCAGGGAGGGAGGCUGUCCUGGCCCUCCUCUCUCUUUUCUUUCUGCCUCUAUGGGGGUGGGGGUAUUGGGGGAACUUGGGGCCGUUCUGGGGUAGCUAAGCCCCUUUCAGCAGGAGAUUGGGGGACCAGUGUUGGGGGCAUCCUGGUGAUGGCCGAUUCCUGCCUCGUCACAUGCCAGGCAGAUGUUCCCGACUCGGCUGGACCCAGCUGCCUCGUUUCCUCCCUUACUUUGCUCUGAGGGGGUGGAAAACAAGGCUUCUCUUUCUGCCCUGGACAGCUACCAGCACCCGGGGUAGGGGAUCCCCUGGUCACCAGUCUUGGCCCAGUACAGGAAAAGGAAUCCGCUUUGUGGCCACAGAUGGGGGCUGGGGAUGGAAGCAGACCUCAGAUCCUGCAUCUCUUCACCCGCUGGACACAGGAGGGCUAUGAACCACUGUGCCGUGGCUGCACCACUGGCUGGAGCAGAGCCAGGCCUGGGAGAGGCAGGUGGCCCCAUCGGCCCCUGCUCUGCACCACCCCUCCCAGAUGACAGAGCCAUAUGUCUUCCACGUGUCUACACACUCACAGACUCACGAAUGUAAUCGCUCAGUCUCACAACAAGCACACGCAGUCACACACCUGCCCACAGGCACAUACGCCACAUAAGCAUGCCUGUAUGCUCACACAGUCAUACUGCCACACGCUAUUACACAUUCACAGCCACAGCCACACAUGCCUUGCCAUCCAUUCAAAGCACCAGUGGCUACUUUGUCAGACACAGCCACACCACAGUCCUAUGCACAUGGUCAUAGCCUCACACAGUGACACAUACUCGGGCACACACCGCCACAAAGCCAUGCUUGCACAGAGCAAAGGUGUCAUAAGCAUCUCUGUGCCUGGACUGCACCUGCAUGACCUCCCAGGGUCCCCACCUCAUCAGAGAUUAAGGAGAGCUUUGCUUGGAGACACCACCCCUGGAGGGGGUGUCUCCAAGGGGGAGUAGAGCCAGUCACAAGCACCACAUACAGGCACACAGCCUGAGGUCUAGGGAUGCAAUUGGGAUGACUGGAUACCACCAAGUUCAGCUCCUUAUUGAACAGAUGGGCGCCUGAGGCCCAGGGAGCAGUGGUGGCUGGCCUUAUCACCCAGCAGGGCAGGGGAUACUCUGGGGCCAGAGCCUGGCUCUGGGCAGACUCUGUUUCCUGGCCCUGCCCUCCCCUGGGCCAAUCCUCUGGGCCAGGCUGCCUCUGAAGGCCCCUGGCUGAACCGAUCCAGCAGAGCUCCAGGCAGCUCCCUUCUCAAGCUAGAGCUGAGCUGCAGUGGCCACGGGAGCCGGAGCCAGGAUGCGGUGGGCAGGGCCUAGGCCUGGGCGGGAGGAACAUUCCUGCACCAUCUCCUCCCCAAGCAUGUGAGGACCCAGCCCGCCCUGCCCGCCUGCCCGCUGACUCAGGCCUCCAGGAGCCAAGCCUGCUCAGCUCCCCCACCCACCCUAACCUGCUUCCCCACUAGUUCGGCUCUGGUUCCCCUCUCCACUGGCUGGGGCAGGAGAAGACGGUGAGCCCUGGUAGGAAGACCAUGGGGAAAAAUCAAACCUCACCACCCCCCGACAUAGCUCAGAAGGGCUGAUUGUGAAACCCAGCUCUGUUCAACAUAGUUGAACACAAACUUUUUUUUUCUUUUGGUUUGGUUUUGUUUUGUUGGUCAAACCCCAGUGCAGUGCAGUCUGUUUAAGAAGUAGUGUCGCAUAGCUGUGGCCUGGAUCUGCUCAGCAGCCCCAGUAGGCAGCAUUUAUUCCCUUUCGCAACAAAGAGACUGAGACUUGGCCAGAGGGAAGAUGGGACCUGCCUAGGUUCACACAGGGAAUCUCUGGCGGGGCUGGACUCAAACCCAGCUCCCUGCCAUCACUCCUUAGAGUCACACUGAUGAACUCAUUUAGGGCCAAAGGAAGAAGGGGAGGCAGAUUUCCCCUCUAGAUGAGUGAAGGGAUAGGAGGCUGGUGAACCCAACGGCUGAAAUGUGAAGGGUGAGAGGGUAGGGUGAGUCCCCCCAGCCCUGAGGGAUGAAGGGUCUGAAGAUGGCACUGCACGGUGACAGCUGCAGUGACUCAGGAGCUCCGUUUACAAAGGAACAUGAGUGAGGAACAUAACUUAAUUUUUUUUUAUAUCUGACCUGAAUUUCUGUUUUCCUCCCCCAUUCCCCACAUGGUAGAAGUGUAAUCUCACAUCAAUUUGGGGACCCUUUCUUUCCCCAGGGAUGUGUAGAACUUUUGGGGAUGGCACAUUUGAAGACCUUAGGGAGCUUUGCAUUUUAAAGGCUGAAUCCCACACUCUAUCAUACAUAUUAAUAUUUACCUGCAUUCCACAUUAAAGGGUUCAGUUUAUGACUUGUGUCCUGUCUUGUAGAUACUUAAUUAAACGGUAUUAAUUUUGA